GAAGACCAUCAUCCCUGGACUACGUUAGGAGGAAGUGGCACCGCUCCGAGGUAGGGGAAGAAGGGUUAUAAAGGGGGGAGUCCACCACACAUGGUCUUGAAGAAGCUUUUAUAAAAGGCAAAGGCAUCUUUGCCGGACGUUGUUGCAAAGGAGUAGAAACAAGCAGACGAAAACAUCCCAAAGGGUAACCACUAGCGUUCCUGCUUCUUGCAACAUUCAUCCCAGGCUUCCAGCUCAGCCCGCCCCAGGCUAGGUGAUCGGUCGCCACAUCCCCUGCGACUGAAGCACCUGCUCCUCCAUGAACCUGCCAAGAGCUGAGCGCCUUCGCUCCACACCGCAGCGCAGCCUCCGGGACUCCGAUGGGGAAGACGGUAAAAUCGAUGUCCUGGGAGAGGAGGAAGAUGAAGACGAGGUGGAAGACGAGGAGGAGGCGGCGAGCCAGCAGUUCCUAGAGCAGUCGCUCCAGCCGGGGCUGCAGGUGGCCCGGUGGGGCGGGGUUGCGCUUCCCCGAGAGCACAUCGAGGGCGGCGGCGGCCCGAGCGACCCCUCAGAGUUUGGCACCAAGUUCAGGGCACCGCCAAGGUCUGCGGCGGCCUCUGAAGAUGCCCGGCAGCCGGCAAAGCCCCCCUACUCGUACAUCGCGCUCAUCACCAUGGCCAUCCUGCAAAACCCGCACAAGCGCCUCACGCUCAGCGGCAUCUGCGCCUUCAUUAGUGGCCGCUUCCCCUACUACCGCCGCAAGUUCCCCGCCUGGCAGAACAGCAUCCGCCACAACCUCUCGCUGAACGACUGCUUCGUUAAGAUCCCCCGCGAGCCGGGCCACCCAGGCAAGGGCAACUACUGGAGCCUGGACCCCGCCUCCCAAGACAUGUUCGACAAUGGCAGCUUUCUCCGGCGUAGGAAGCGUUUCAAGCGCCACCAACUGACCCCGGGAGCCCACCUGCCCCACCCCUUCCCUCUACCUGCUGCACACGCCGCCCUGCACAACCCCCACCCAGGCCCUCUGCUUGGGGCCCCUGCCCCGCCGCAGCCAGUCCCGGGGGCCUACCCCAACACCGCCCCCGGGAGACGCCCUUACGCUCUGCUGCACCCGCAUCCUCUUCGCUACCUACUGCUCUCGGCCCCCGUCUAUGCCGGGGCACCGAAGAAAGCAGAAGGCGCGGCCCUGGCGACCCCGGCACCCUUCCCGUGCUGCAGCCCUCACUUGGUCCUCAGCCUUGGGAGGAGGGCAAGGGUCUGGCGUCGCCACCGGGAGGCGGAUGCAUCUCUUUCAGCAUUGAGAGUAUUAUGCAAGGGGUCAGGGGAGCGGGUACAGGGGCUGCGCAGAGUUUGUCCCCGACCGCGUGGAGCUACUGCCACCUGCUCCAGCGACCAUCAAGCCUGUUGCAUCCCCAGACCGCUGCCCCUUUGCUGCAAGUGUCCGCCGCCGCCGCUGCUCGGACAAUUUUGCAGCAAUAGCAGCAGCAUCAGGAGGAGGACUGCGCCAACGGCUGCGCUCCCACCAAGGGCGCGGUGCUGGGCGGGCACCUGUCGGCCUCGUCGGCCCUGCUGAGGUAUCAGGCAGUGGCAGAGGGCUCUAGGCUGACAUCGCUGGCUGCCCCUUUGGGCGGAGAGGGGACCUCACCAGUUUUUUUAGUAUCGCCCACGCCCAGUUCCCUGGCCAACUCCGCAGGGCCCUCCUAGAGCCAGGUGGGAGUGGGGAGCGACCCGCAGCUGCUCACUUCACCUUGCGCGGCCCAUUCAGGGCGUGUGCAUCUGAAUCCCGCUGGAGAGCAAACACGAACUUCUGUUCGCUGCAAAAUGGUUAGAAAGAAACAGCUGGAUUACGUUCCUCUAAAAACCACCUGAACGUAACCUUCGCAGGGCGUCAAGUCAUCUUUUCUUGCCUUCGGUUGUGGCUUCUAUGGCUGUCCCGAUUUGCGCAUUUCCUGGGGUACUAUGAACGUGAGUGGGGUAUUUUGUUCUGGCAUUAAAAGAAAAACAAGCAAGCAAACAAAAACACAGCCUCCGAUGCCAAACAUGUUCCCCCUUCUUCACUUCCUUGGAGCUGGAAGUAUUAUUCCUAAGUCUAGUGCAAAAUGCUUCUACUCUCUGUGUCUUCCUGAUAGGGAUGUUUAAUGUAAGUAGGAUAUUAAUUUCAGAACAUUGAUUUCUUAUCUGUGUGUCUGACGUGCCAUCUUUAAUGUUAAAAUUAAGGUGUUAAAAUUAAGCCUAGUUAUAUAGACGAAAUAAAAUGCUAAGUCACUA